GCACGCGCAUGCUGCACGCGGAUUGGAAACCCGGAGUUACCUGCUAGUUGGUGAAACUGGUUGGUAGACGUGAUCUGCUCGCUACUACCGGCCUCCCCAGGCUGUUAAAAGCAGAUGGUAGCUGAGGUUGAUUCAAUGCCGGCUGCCUCUUCUGUGAAGAAGCCAUUUGUUCUCAGGAGCAAGAUGGGCAAGUGGUGCCGCCACUGCUUCCCCUGCUGCAGGGGGAGCGGCAAGAGCAACGUGGGCACUUCUGGAGACCAGGACGACUCCACUAUGAAGACACUCAGGAGCAAGAUGGGCAAGUGGUGCUGCCACUGCUUCCCCUGCUGCAGGGGGAGCGGCAAGAGCAACGUGGGUGCUUGGGGAGACUACGACGACAGCGCCUUCGUGGAGCCGAGAUACCACGUCCGUCGAGAAGAUCUGGACAAGCUCCACAGAGCUGCCUGGUGGGGUAAAGUCGCCAGAAAGGAUCUGAUCGUCAUGCUCAGGGACACUGACGUGAACAAGCAGGACAAGCAAAAGAGGACUGCUCUACAUCUGGCCUCUGCCAAUGGGAAUUCAGGAGUAGUAAAACUCCUGCUGGACAGACGAUGUCAACUUAAUGUCCUUGACAACAAAAAGAGGACAGCUCUGACAAAGGUAUGCAGUAGCCAACUAUAUCAGCAUGAGGCCGUACAAUGCCAGGAAGAUGAAUGUGCGUUAAUGUUGCUGGAACAUGGCACUGAUCCAAACAUUCCAGAUGAGUAUGGAAAUACCACUCUACACUACGCUAUCUACAAUGAAGAUAAAUUAAUGGCCAAAGCACUGCUCUUAUACGGUGCUGAUAUCGAAUCAAAAAACAAGCAUGGCCUCACACCACUGCUACUUGGUGUACAUGAGCAAAAACAGCAAGUGGUGAAAUUUUUAAUCAAGAAAAAAGCGAAUUUAAAUGCACUGGAUAGAUAUGGAAGAACUGCUCUCAUACUUGCUGUAUGUUGUGGAUCAGCAAGUAUAGUCAGCCUUCUACUUGAGCAAAAUAUUGAUGUAUCUUCUCAAGAUCUAUCUGGACAGACGGCCAGAGAGUAUGCUGUUUCUAGUCAUCAUCAUGUAAUUUGCCAGUUACUUUCUGACUACAAAGAAAAACAGAUGCUAAAAAUCUCUUCUGAAAACAGCAAUCCAGAACAAGACUUAAAGCUGACAUCAGAGGAAGAGUCACAAAGGUUCAAAGGCAGUGAAAAUAGCCAGCCAGAGAAAAUGUCUCAAGAACCAGAAAUAAAUAAGGAUGGUGAUAGAGAGGUUGAAGAAGAAAUGAAGAAGCAUGAAAGUAAUAAUGUGGGAUUACUAGAAAACCUGAGUAAUGGUGUCACUGCUGGCAAUGGUGAUGAUGGAUUAAUUCCUCAAAGGAAGAGCAGAACACCUGAAAAUCAGCAAUUUCCUGACAACGAAAGUGAAGAGUAUCACAGAAUUUGCGAAUUAGUUUCUGACUACAAAGAAAAACAGAUGCCAAAAUACUCUUCUGAAAACAGCAACCCAGAACAAGACUUAAAGCUGACAUCAGAGGAAGAGUCACAAAGGCUUAAAGGCAGUGAAAAUGGCCAGCCAGAGAAAAGAUCUCAAGAACCAGAAAUAAAUAAGGAUGGUGAUAGAGAGCUAGAAAAUUUUAUGGCUAUCGAAGAAAUGAAGAAGCACGGAAGUACUCACGUCGGAUUCCCAGAAAACCUGACUAAUGGUGCCACUGCUGGCAAUGGUGAUGAUGGAUUAAUUCCUCCAAGGAAGAGCAGAACACCUGAAAGCCAGCAAUUUCCUGACACUGAGAAUGAAGAGUAUCACAGUGACGAACAAAAUGAUACUCAGAAGCAAUUUUGUGAAGAACAGAACACUGGAAUAUUACACGAUGAGAUUCUGAUUCAUGAAGAAAAGCAGAUAGAAGUGGUUGAAAAAAUGAAUUCUGAGCUUUCUCUUAGUUGUAAGAAAGAAAGAGACUUCUUGCAUGAAAAUAGUAUGUUGCGGGAAGAAAUUGCCAUGCUAAGACUGGAGCUAGACACAAUGAAACAUCAGAGCCAGCUAAGAAAAAAGAAAUAUUUGGAGGAUAUUGAAAGUGUGAAAAAAAAGAAUGAUAAUCUUUUAAAGGCUCUACAAUUGAAUGAGCUCACCAUGGAUGAUGAUACCGCUGUGCUCGUCAUUGACAACGGCUCUGGCAUGUGCAAGGCCGGCUUUGCGGGCGACGAUGCCCCCCGGGCUGUCUUCCCUUCCAUCGUGGGGUGCCCCAGGCAGCAGGGCAUGAUGGGGGGCAUGCAUCAGAAAGAGUCCUAUGUGGGCAAGGAGGCCCAGAGCAAGAGAGGCAUCCUGACCCUGAAGUACCCCAUGGAACACGGCAUCAUCACCAACUGGGAUGACAUGGAGAAGAUCUGGCACCACACCUUCUACAACGAGCUGCGUGUGGCCCCCGAGGAGCACCCCAUCCUGCUGACCGAGGCCCCCCUGAACCCCAAGGCCAACCGCGAGAAGAUGACCCAGAUCAUGUUUGAGACCUUCAACACCCCAGCCAUGUACGUGGCCAUCCAGGCCAUGCUGUCCCUGUACACCUCUGGCCGUACUACUGGCAUCGUGAUGGACUCUGGUGACGGGGUCACCCACACUGUGCCCAUCUAUGAUGGGAAUGCCCUCCCCCAUGCCACCCUGCGCCUAGACCUGGCUGGGCGGGAACUGACUGACUACCUCAUGAAGAUCCUCACCGAGCGUGGCUAUAGGUUCACCACCAUGGCCGAGCGGGAAAUCGUGCGUGACAUCAAAGAGAAGCUGUGCUAUGUUGCCCUGGACUUCGAGCAGGAGAUGGCCAUGGUGGCCUCCAGCUCCUCCCUAGAGAAGAGCUACGAGCUGCCCGAUGGCCAGGUCAUCACCAUCAGCAACGAGUGGUUCCGCUGCCCCGAGGCGCUCUUCCAGCCUUGCUUCCUGGGCAUGGAAUCCUGUGGCAUCCAUGAAACUACCUUCAACUCCAUCAUGAAGUCUGAUGUGGACAUCCGCAAAGACCUGUACACCAACACAGUGCUGUCUGGCGGCACCACCAUGUACCCUGGCAUGGCCCACAGAAUGCAGAAGGAGAUCGCUGCCCUGGCGCCUAGCAUGAUGAAGAUCAGGAUCAUUGCUCCUCCCAAGCGCAAGUACUCCGUGUGGGUCGGUGGCUCCAUCCUGGCCUCGCUGUCCACCUUCCAGCAGAUGUGGAUCAGCAAGCAGGAGUAUGAUGAGUCAGGCCCCUCCAUUGUCCACCGCAAAUGCUUCUAGGUGGACUCUGACUUAGUUGCGUUACACCCUUUCUUGACAAAACCAAACUUCUCAGAAAACAACAUGAGAUUGGCAUGGCUUUAUUUGUUUUCUUGUUUCAUUUUUUGUUUUGUUUUUUAUUGGCUUGACUCAGGAUUUAAAAACCGGAAUGGUGAAGGUG